AGUUUAAUUACGUCCCCGGGAACUGCGCCGAUUUGGACUUUUGGCACUUGGACCUAUGCUUUAAAAAGAAAAAAGUGUCAUUGGCGUGGAGUGGGGCUAGUGGAGGGUGAGGUGAAUGCGCCGUUUGGAAACCACAGGACAGUGAACGUUUCGUCUCUCCCAGCGAGACUCUCCCGCGGGCCCGGCGGCCGCAUCGGGAGCCCGGCGGAAACAUGGCGGCGCCCGGAGGCCGGGGCCGCAGCCUCUCCGGCCUGCUCCCCGCGCAGACCUCGCUAGAGUACGCCCUGCUCGACGCCGUUACCCAGCAGGAGAAGGACAGCCUGGUCUACCAGUAUCUGCAGAAGGUGGACGGCUGGGAGCAGGACUUGUCAGUACCCGAGUUUCCGGAAGGAUUAGAAUGGCUGAACACAGAAGAACCUAUUUCUGUCUACAAGGAUCUAUGUGGAAAAAUAGUCGUCCUUGAUUUCUUCACCUACUGCUGCAUAAACUGUAUUCACCUAUUGCCUGAUCUCCAUGCAUUAGAACACACAUACUCUGAUAAAGAUGGUCUUCUUAUUAUUGGUGUUCACUCGGCUAAGUUUCCAAAUGAAAAAGUCCUGGAUAACAUUAAGAGUGCUGUUCUUCGAUACAACAUCACCCACCCUAUGGUUAAUGAUGCAGAUGCCAGCCUUUGGCAAGAACUAGAAGUUUCCUGCUGGCCAACUCUAGUCAUACUUGGACCUCGUGGAAACAUGUUGUUUUCUUUGAUUGGAGAGGGACACAAAGAUAAAUUAUUUUUAUAUACUUCAAUUGCUUUAAAGUAUUACAAAGACAGGGGGCAGAUCAGAGAUAAUAAAAUUGGAAUAAAACUCUAUAAAGAUUCUUUGCCACCUUCACCAUUGCUAUUUCCUGGCAAAGUAACAGUAGACCAAGUUACUGAUAGAUUGGUAAUAGCAGACACUGGACAUCAUAGAAUUUUGGUCGUUUGGAAGAAUGGACAAAUUCAAUAUAGCAUUGGAGGACCCAACCCUGGAAGAAAAGAUGGAAUAUUUUCAGAAUCAACUUUUAAUUCUCCACAGGGUGUAGCCAUAAUGAAUAAUAUCAUAUAUGUGGCAGACACUGAAAACCACCUUAUAAGAAAGAUUGACCUAGAAGCUGAGAAGGUGAGCACUGUAGCUGGUAUUGGAAUUCAAGGUACAGAUAAAGAAGGUGGAGCAAAAGGAGAACAACAACCCAUUAGUUCCCCUUGGGAUGUAGUUUUUGGAACAUCAGGUUCAGAGGUCCAAAGAGGUGACAUUUUAUGGAUAGCCAUGGCAGGGACUCAUCAGAUAUGGGCACUCCUGCUGGACUCUGGCAAACUGCCAAAGAAAAAUGAGUUAACAAAAGGAACCUGCCUUAGGUUUGCUGGAAGUGGAAAUGAAGAGAAUCGAAACAAUGCCUAUCCUCACAAGGCAGGUUUUGCCCAACCUUCAGGCCUUUCCUUGGCCUCUGAAGAUCCCUGGAGCUGCUUGUUUGUAGCAGAUAGUGAGAGCAGUACAGUGAGAACCGUUUCACUGAAAGAUGGAGCAGUGAAGCACCUCGUAGGAGGAGAAAGAGACCCCAUGAAUUUAUUUGCUUUUGGUGAUGUUGAUGGAGUAGGAAUCAAUGCAAAGCUUCAACACCCCCUUGGAGUAACAUGGGACAAAAAAAGGAAUUUACUUUAUGUUGCAGACUCCUACAAUCACAAGAUUAAAGUUGUGGAUCCAAAAACAAAAAACUGUACAACAUUAGCAGGAACUGGAGACACAAAUAAUGUUACCAGUUCCAGUUUUACAGAGUCAACUUUUAAUGAACCAGGAGGCUUGUGUAUUGGAGAGAAUGGAGAAUUAUUAUAUGUAGCAGACACCAAUAAUCAUCAAAUUAAAGUGAUGGAUUUAGAAACUAAAAUGGUAUCUGUGCUCCCCAUCUUCAGAUCUGAAAAUGCUGUGGUAGAUGGCCCGUUCCUAGUAGAAAAACAGAAGACAUUACCCAAACUACCUAAAUCUGCUCCAAGCAUUAGGCUUUCCCCCGUGACUGCGUGUGCUGGCCAGACUCUUCAGUUCAAACUCAGAUUAGACCUCCCAUCAGGAUCAAAGCUAACUGAAGGAGUAUCCAGUUGCUGGUUUCUAACAGCUGAAGGCAAUGAAUGGCUACUUCAAGGACAGAUAGCAGCUGGAGAUAUAGAGAACAUUUCCAGUCAACCAACAAUUUCACUACAAAUUCCUGAUGAUUGCUUAUCACUUGAAGCCAUUGUAUCUGUCAGUGUGUUUCUUUAUUACUGUAGUGCAGACAGCAGUGCUUGUAUGAUGAAGGCAAUUUUGUUCAGUCAGCCUUUACAAAUAACGGAUACACAGCAAGGUUGCAUAGCUCCAGUAGAGCUCAGGUAUGUAUUUUAGCCAGCCAGCUAGCUAGCAACCCAUUGCCACCACCUACUGUCUCCCAUCCUGACUAUCACUGUAAUUUAAGGAAAGAAAACUUCAGUUCUGCCUCUGGAUACCAAGAUGCCCAUUGCUCAGUUCAGACAACUGAUAUUAAAAUAAAGCUAUGCUCCUUACUUACUUCUUUUAUUAUAAACAAAUUCCUUUGCUUUGGCUGAUACUAGCUGAGUCAUUGAUCAUCAUUGGUACCAUGAUAUUGUAAUCUAUGCUGCUAUUUGGCACAAGACUGAAGUUCACACUACAGUAGAGAAUACUAUAAGAUAAUUUGCAAUAAAUACUGAUAAUAAUAAUACCAGAUAUUUUAACUAACUUUUUCUACCUUUAUUAAUAGCAAUCAGCACACUUGAAUGUGUAAAUUUCACAGUAACUUUAGGCAGAACUUAAGCUCCAGGCCACAUUUGUAUAAGAACACCAAGUAUUCAAGGCAUAAAGUCUGUUGUAAGCCAAAAAAAAGUCUUUUCAUCACUGUAGAAGCUUAAGGAGUACAUCAGUGGUAAAUACGAUCUUUAUUCUCUUCUGUGGUUUUCUCAGUUGAGAUAUUUUUAAAAGAGAGUUUUGAUCUAUUUUUAUUAUAAAUUAUUUGUUAUUUAACAUACCAUUAUGAAUGCCUUAAAACUUUGUACAGAUAAAGUUGGACAUAGAAUCUCUAAGGACUGACUCCUUUAACUGUUUUUGAGUGACUACAUUACCAGAUAAUGAAUGAGUCCCCAGAAAUAUUAUGACUUUCAAGGAAAAAGGGACUUUAGGACACAUUACUUAGUGUCUGUGAUAAAUAAUUUAUUGUGACAGCUAAAUCUGAUGGUUACAUAUCUUGUUUUGGAAAUGUACAUUUCACUUGUAAGCAUUAAAUGCAGAUUUGUUGAGUUUAGGUUUUGAGGUUUUUUUCGUUCCCAUAUUCAGAAUUUAAAUUAUGAUCAUUUAUUGUGAUGUUUUUAAAAAUCACUUUUAAGCCUUAAAAGUGAAAUUUUCAGUGUGAGGUGCUUUCAUGCUAUUAAUAGAUACAGUAUAUCCUAAUAUAUUAGUCUUCAAAAUAUUAAGGCCGAAACAGUGAUUUAAUGAUACUAUUUUUUAAUUUUUGUUGUUUUUUAUCCCUAAAAAAAGAUAUUGGAAAGGUUUUUUUUCUAUUGUCAUAAUUUAUAACUACUUAAAAGCCUAAUCUUGUUUUCCUUAAGACCUAUUCAACAUGUUUGUGAUUUAAUCAGCUUACAAGGGUUUAAAAACAUCAGGUGAACCAUGUUUAUUUAUUCAGUAAAUAUUUAUAGACAAUAUGGCAUAAUAUGCUUCCCUUCCCUGUAAAAACAGUGCUAAAUUUGAAGUGUAAUCUUUUUUAAACAUCAUUGUCUAUUUUUAAUUUUGUUUGAAAUGUAGUAUUAGUUUGUUUUAUUCAUAAGGUUAGCUGAAUCUCUGAAGUAAGGAUGUAUAAAUCAUGACAUUGAUUUAAUUAGUCAUCUACUGAAGCUACUUUUAAAGAGAAAUAUAGAUAUAAAAUUAAAAGGAAUCCUGUUUAAAAUUAUAUGUAAUUACCUCAUAAACCUUUUCUCUCCACAAGCAAUCAAAAAAAUGAAAUGUUCUGUAAUAAAAGGGUGUAUAACAUACUCUCUUUUAUGAGAAUAGGCCUUAGUUAUUUUAUUUUAUUUUUGAGACGUAGUCUGGCUCUGUAGCCCAGGCUGGGAGGGCAGUGGCGCGAUCUUGGCUCACUGCAACCUCUACCUCCUGGGUUCAAGAGAUUUUCCUGCCUCAGCCUCCCAAGUAGCUGGGAUUACAGGCGUACACCACCAUGCCCAGCUAAUUUUUUUGUGUUUUUAGUAGAGACAGGGUUUCACCAUGUCAGUCAGGCUGGUCCCAAACUCCUGGCCUCAGGUGAUCCGCCUGCCUCUGUCUCCCAAAGUGCUGGGAUUACAGGUGUGAGCCACCUUGCCCUACUGGCCUUAGUUAAUUUUUAAUCUCAUUUGACUUAUUAUGUUUCUCAUUUCUAGAUGGACAGGAUGAGAAUAUUUUGGCCCAAUCAUUUUCUGUUUAAGGACUUAAACAAUUUCACACUCUAAAUGAAGUAUAUACAAUUUUAAUUUACUAAUUUAGAAAUAUCUGAGUUUAUUUUUCAAUAUAAUAUACAAACACAGUGUUUGUUAUACAUGUUCAUGUACAGUGAAAAUGCAAAGGCAUUUUUUAGACUCUAUUCCCCUUCAUUUGUCUAGACAGUUUUAGGUUAGCCUUAGCUUAUACUUUUCUUGACUUUCAAAAUACAGUUUUAUUGAACAUUCUUAUUCUUACCCACUGCCAGUCUGCAUUGUUUUUUACAUUAAAAGUAUUAUUUAUAGUAGACUAAUAUGAUUUUGAAUAAAAUCACACUUAAGCAAUAUAGAUAGGUUCCUAGAAUUUAUGACGAGGAUAAACCUCUCACAUAAGAGGAAGCACUAGAAAGUUUAUUUUUAAAACUUGUUGAUCCAUAUUCUAUAAGGACUAAUGCAUAUUUUUUAUCUUUUGCUUUUCUUGUUGGAUAAAUUAUUAUGUCCAGUGAUAGUUUAAAAAGAACAAGAUUUUAGUGUAAGUCACCUCACUUGAAAUGCCAGUAAUGUGGUAUUACACACAUUUUAUAUAAUACCUGGAAUCUUUGCCCUAAAUUAUUCUGCUGGUUUGUCGCUAUUUUUUUCCUCUCCUCUUUAUUAUUUCACAAAUGGUAGAAUUUCUUGAUAUGAUUCUUGUAAAGAGUUUAGCUUAUCUUGAACAUUCUGUCUUAAGCAAAUAUUUAACAAGAGAAAACUUUGUAGUUUAAUCACCCAUAAGUGUAACUUUAGCAAAAUUCAAUGACUAUGAAAAAUAAUUUUUUUCUUAACUGUUCUAAUAAUAUUUAGUUAUAAUAUUAUCAAACCUUCAGAAAGUUAUAAAUCCUAACAGCCAGAAAAAAAAAUUUACUAUGUGUAUAUUUAUAUAGGUGUGUGUAUACACAAAGAUUAAGAAUUAUUCAUGAUUCUUUUAUGGCCAAUAUACUUUUGAGCUUGUAUAACUGAGAUAAGUUACUCUUUGCUUGUUUUUCUGUAGUUGGAAAAUUUAGGAAGUUAUUAAAAAUACAUAUCUCUAUAAUGUAAUAGUUUUCUGCCUGCACAAAGUUUACUAUUAAUUUAUGUCUACCAGUUAAAAAUACGAUAGUUAGAUUUGGCAUCACGUUUAACCACAAUCAUCAAAAUCUACUUAAAUUCUAUAGUUAACAGUUACAUAAGAAUAUAUGCAGAGGGAAAAUGUCAAUAGUUCUUGUGAAUGAAGGAAUUAUGGAUGUUUUUAUUUUAAUUCUACUUUGCUGUUUUUUUUUUCUUUUCAGUGAGCAAUCUGUUAUUUUUAAAAUCACGGUGGGGGGAAACCCAUAAAGUUUAAAGAGUUAAAGUUAACUGAAUCGUAAGCACUUAUAUAAUAACUUUUUAAAAGUCAUUUUUAUUACCAGAGCUCAGAACAUUGUUUGGAGUCCUUUGAUCUACCGGUUCUCUUAAGUACGUGAUUUCGUGAAGAUAGCAAUGGUUAUGGCUUUUUUGUUCUGUUAUUUUUAUUGUGUAACGUAGUGUAGUGGUUAAGAGCUUGGAUUUUGCAGUAACUUGGAUUCUAAUCCUUUAAAAUGGGGCUGAUAUACCUGCCUCAUAUUCAAUGAAAUAUUGUGUGUACAGCACUUAGUAAUUAAUGAAACUGGUAAUUAUUAGCUUAGUUACUGUAAUGAUAAUUUGGGACCAUAAACACAUAUCACCCUACAUUUUCUUUGCAACUACAAUUUGUGAAGGAAAAUCUCCCACUAACUAUUGGUUAUGUUAAUAUUCUUCAUAGAGUUGGGUUCAAGAAGAGAAAUGUUUUAUAAUGAAGCAUAUAACUAUUUUAUAAACAACAUUGUAGUUAUAAAGAAGCAUGCCUAUAGUGUUAUUAAAAAUUUUUUGUACGACUUUCUGGAGCUACAAGUAAUGAACUUGCUUUGAGAGGGUCCAGACAUACUCAUCCUGAACCACAUUCCUACAACAUAUGCCCAACAACCUGCACCAGAGUACUUAUAUCUUAACCAAAAAGUUUCACUUCAAUGGUGGUGCUUCACAAAAUCUUCAAAGUGCUUUCAUGUGUAUUGCCUCAUUUGAGCUUCAAAUAACCUUAUAAAUCGGGCAGGUAGAUGUUAGUUUACAGAGGAGGAGACAGCUUUGGAAUAGUGGUGACGUAUCUGAAGAAUAGAAAACCGGAAUAGUGCUCGAUGCCUGAAGUGGUGCCUGGCGCCAGCAGAUGUUCACUUCUGUCAAACAAGGGGAAGUAGUGGUGGAGCCUUUAUUCAGGCACGGGUCUCCUCAUUCCUAACUCCAAGAUGCAGAGGGAAAACGAACUGCUCAAUUAAGAGUUCUUCCAUGGACACUUUCUUAAGCCUUCACAUAAAAUAACAAGAAUAAUAGAUAUUUAUUGAGUAGAUAUUUAUUGAGUUCUUUCUAUUUUCCAGCACUCAUCUAUUAAGUGCUUUUAUGUAUUAACUCAUUUAAUCCACACAACAACCUUAUGUGAGAAAUACCAUUUUUCCUUAUUUGAUUGGUGAAGAAGCACACAGAGAGGGUAAGCAUAAUCAAAUACACCAGCAUAACCAAAAUCACACAUUUAGCGAGUGGCAGGGCCUGGAUGGGAGUCUGUUCAACUCUCUGCUGUAUUGCCUCUUAAAGUAGGUUUUCUUAAAACAUAAAUCUUUCAUAACUUUAUAUAUUUAUAGUAACUUAAUCCAAAGAACCCCAAAAGUACUAGCAAUGAUUGUUUCUGCAAUUUAAAUAAAUCCAUUUAAUUAUACAACUUUGCAUUAUAUACUGUUAUUCAGACCUUGGAACAGUCUAUAAUUGUUUGUCAAAAGAUUUUAUGUACUACUUUUUCUUAAUUUCAGAUAUUAUCCAGAGUUUUUCUUGGCAGAUGGAUGUAUUAAAAAAAUAGCUUUCCAGUGUUAGUUCUCAACAGUGCUGUUUCAAAAGUUGUUUUAAAAGUUCUAACGGUUGGUCUUCAAAACGUAAUUAAGACCUUAUCAUAAAGAGCCUUUUGCACAGGACUAUCUCAAACCCUAAGAAGCUAUUCAUAUUUAAGAAAAUUUUGUUGUAUUAAAUAUUAGUCCAAGUGAGCUCUGGAAAUACAGUCUUCUGCUUUCUUGUUUCAUAAAUAACACUGGUAUGCAGACCCCUCCCCAUGACUCAAAUAUUAAUAUAUGCAAUUCUGUUACAGUAAAGUUUUCACCAUGGUCAACCUAUUCCAGCAUUAGGUACUUUUUGUUGUUGUUGUUUUGUUUUUUUUUUUUUUUUUUGAGAUGGAGUCUCACUCUGUCACCCAGGCUGGAGUGCAAGGGUACAAUCUCAGCUCACUGCAGGCUCCACCUACCGGGUUCAAGUGAUCCUCCUGCCUCAGCCUCCCAAGUAGCUGGCGCUCACCACUACUGGUGCCCACCACAAUGCCCGGCUAAUUUUUGUACUUUUAGUAGAAACAGGGUUUCUGUUGGCCAGGUUGGUCUCGAACUCCUGACCUCAUGUGAUGCGCCUGCCUUGGCCUCCCAAAGUGCUGGGAUUACAGGCGUGAGCCACCGUACCCAGCCUAGCAUUAGGUACUUUGUUUUGUUUUGUUUUGUUUUUGUUUUUUUUGAGAUGGAGUUUUGCUCUUGUUGCCCAGGCUGGAGUGCCAUGGCAACACAGCCUCCACUUCCUGUGUUCAAGCAAUUCUCCUGCCUCAGCCUCCUGAGUAGCUGGGAUUACAGGCGUCUGCCACCACGCUUAGCUGAUUUUUUGUAUUUUUAGUGGAGAUGGGGUUUCGCCAUGCUUGCCAGGCUGGUCUCGAACUCCUGACCUCAGGUGAUCUGCCUGCCUUGGCCUUCCAAAGUGCUGGGAUUACAGGCGUGAGCCGCUGCGCCCAGCGCACUAAAUACUAUUAAAAGGAAUUAAGCAAAAUGCUACGUACCAAUGAUUAUGAUUCAUGAUCACCUAAACACAGAAUGCAGACUUAACUUUUCAUUCUUAGUGUGCUAAUUAAGUAGUAGUAUGGUGCAGUAAGGAAUUUUGUUAAUUUUGUUAUAAACUCCCUCUCCUGAAAUCCGUAAGGAAAUGUGAUAAUAAGAAAGUGAUAAUAGUGUCAUAUUUUAAAAGUAGAAUCCACUGUUAAGCACCAAGAUUACCUUUUCUUCCCCCUGUGGCACAGUUUAUUUAAAUGAAGUAUUAGCAAUAAUCAUGUCACUAUUUUGUCCUGAAUAAUUAAGAGUUUGCUUUUUUCCCAUGUCUUUGCAAUAGGAUAAUAUAAAGAAUAGUAUUAAAAGUCAGAGGCUUUACUAAUCUACCUAUAUGUAUUCCAUGGCUAACAAACCCUGGCCCCUUUACAUAUGAGCUCUGGAGGUUCGCCUGGCUGCCUCAGGCUUGCAGAAGGCUGCCCCAAUCACAGAGCCUGGGUAAGGUGGAACAGGAGGCAGCCCCACUCGGCUUUUCUGAUUGCAUCCCACCUGUUUCUGAGUGUGUUGGUUUGGUUUAAUUCUUUUCAAGGGUUGGAGUUGGAAAGUGAAAACCCUAGACACUUGCUGUGGAAUGUUUGCCUGGUUGUAUUGGUGUGUCCCUCUUCUUCACUGGCAUGUCGCUUUCAAGUGUACCAAAGGACAUUUUGUUCUGUUGAAAGCCACAGGACCAAAAGGAAAAUAUUGCAACUAUUUGCAAACAUACUUCCCUACCUGUACAAGCAGCCAUAUACUAAAAAGCACUAAACAAGCACAAAUGAACACUAAAUAGCCUUAUACCAAAAAGCAUUCUUGUAACUGUCAGGGCAUGGUAUGAAUUCCUUCCUCUUUAAGCAGCAACUUACCACAGGCUUGGUGGCUUUAAGUAAUAUAGCAUUAAGCAAAUGGUCAGUUAUUUUUUAAUGUUGAAAACUUCCAAGUGUGAAUAAUACGGACAUAGUUUACUACCUUUUGCUUUUAAUAUACCUGGUUAUCUAUUUCCAUUUGAAAUAAAAUGAAAGGAGACCUCAAACUGAUGCUGAGAAGUAGACAAAAUCAGCUCUCAGACUUAACUCUCCCCAAUUAAAAUAGUUUUUUUUUCCCUUCCCAUUUUUUUGUUUUUAAGAGAUAGGGUCUUGCUGUGUUGCCCAGGCUAGAGUGCAGCAGUGACAUGAUCAUAGCUCACUGCAGCCUGGAACUCCUGGGCUCAGGAUCCUUCUGCUUCGGCCUCCUGAGUAGCUAAGACCACAGGUGUGUGCCACCACACCUGGCUAAUUUUUUUAAAAUUUUUUGUAGAGAUGGGGACUUGCUAUGUUGCCCAGACUGGUCUCGAACUCCUGGCCUCAAGCCACCAACCUCUCAAAUUGCUAGAAUUACAAGCAUGAGCCACCACACCUGGCCUGUUAUUCCUUCUUUAUCUAAUGUGUGCUAAGCUUGUGAAAAAUAUAUGUUGAGGUAAAUAGGGCAAAACAUUAGUUGAUAAAUUAUGCUAAUUAAUGGGAAAAAUAGACAUGUUCCUCUCUGAACAUUUAGAAGGACUCUGCCCUACAACUAUCUUCUGUUUUUAGAAUUUGUAGUCACUGUUCUUAGUGCCACUGGAAAUAUAUUCAUUCUUUGAGCAUGUACAGGGUGGGCUCCCUGUUGUAUUUAUUACACUUUUCAAAAUGCCAGCAAGUUUUUGUUUGUAUAGAGUUGGAAUGUAUUGUUCGUGCAUGCCUGUGAUAUUCAUCAUCAAAAUAUACCUGUAAAAAAUAAACUACUGCUUCCUCUCCACAGCUUAGGCCUCCCUCUUACUAAAAACAAUAGUAGUUUCUGUAGAAGUUUCAGUGAGAAAUUAUGGUUAUAUAAAUAACAGAUAUGGCAGAACAAUUUUGUUGUAGUAUUUUUUUCCGUAGCAUUUCUUAAUAAUAGCUCAGUUUUUAAAGGAGGGGAACAAUACCCCAUGAGUUCAAAUUAAUUUUCUCUACUUUGAGGUAUACCUUCCUAAUUAUAUUUUACAUAGGCUGUUUUUUUUAAGUUUAAAUUCUCACUGUUAAGUUGCAUUGAGAGACAAUUAGAAAUGUUGUAAUUGUCAUAUCUUUACAUGUGGAUUAUGAACAAAUGAAAGUUUGCUGUGUGAUUGCAGUUUUAAAUUAUAACAUUUCAUAAAUAUGUCAAUUUUAGAAACUCAAACUCUUUCCCAUCUUUUGUAUGGAUAAAGUUUAUGGUUUCAUUUCUGAGAAUAGAGUUGGUCUGCUGUGCUAACUUCAUGUUUCUUAUUCCAAAGGCUUGAUUAUAUUUUUUUCUCCAGUGAUUAAAAAUGCAGCGAAAAUCCAAUCUACAAGUUCAUAUAUUGGUAUUUCUAGACAUAGUCUAGUUCUAAAAGAAUGUACUUGGUGUGCAUUUUUAAGUGUUUCAUGUAGACAGAUUAAUAUAUUUUUGUACAACAUUGUAUUUCUACAUUUAUUUCAAGACUGUACUUUUCAGUGACUUUUUCAAGUGCAUGUGUUAACAGAAGAUUGUUUGGAACGAGAGUGCAGUGGCUUCUUUACUAGCAAAGAGAAGUGUAAUACAAGUGAUCAUAGAAGGUGAGAAUGUGUUUAUACUGUAUAUGGAAACCUAAUGCCUCUUUUCUAAAGCUUUGUACAUUUUUUUCGUGAAAUAGAUUAAAUAUUUUCUCUCUAAAA